GUUUCCGGCGGUGUGGAAGCGGACCUGAGGAGUCGCAAUUGUGAACAGGUUCGGUGCUGCGGCUGGGGCUCAGCGAUAUGAGGCAGCAUCGACAAUUUAUGGACCGCACGCAUUAUCUGCUUACAUUCAGCUCUUCAGAAACCUUGCUAAGGCUAUUGCUACGGAACUUCACUUGUGGAAAUCUUCCCUUUGGAUGCAGUUGUUUAUGAAGCUGCAACUGUGAUGUCAGAAGGACAUGGUAGCCAACCUGAGCAGAGGUCCAGAACCUCCCUUUUUCAAACAAUUAAUAGUUCCAUUAAUUCCUAGUAUUGUGGAUAGAGCACCAAAAGGCAGAACUUUCGGGGAUGUCCUGCAGCCAGCAAAACCUGAAUACAGAGUGGGGGAAGUUGCUGAAGUUAUAUUUGUAGGUGCUAACCCGAAGAAUUCAGUACAAAACCAGACCCAUCAGACCUUCCUCACUGUGGAGAAAUAUGAGGCUACUUCAACAUCGUGGCAGAUAGUGUGUAAUGAUGCCUCCUGGGAGACUCGUUUUUAUUGGCACAAGGGACUCCUGGGUCUGAGUAAUGCAACAGUGGAAUGGCAUAUUCCAGACACUGCCCAGCCUGGAAUCUACAGAAUAAGAUAUUUUGGACACAAUCGGAAGCAGGACAUUCUGAAGCCUGCUGUCAUACUUUCAUUUGAAGGCACUUCCCCGGCUUUUGAAGUUGUAACUAUUUAGUGAAAAGUUGAUAGAUCAUUUAAAGAACAGCUUUACUCUCUACACAUUAUAUAAGUGAUUUCAAAUGAAUGUGAACUAGUGAACUACCAUGUUGACUUCUAUAAUCGUCCCUGUUUGGGGACAGAUAGUUUACUGCUAAUGGGGUGGAGGGGUGUGUGUGUGUGUGUGUGUGUGUGUGUGUGUGUGUGUGUGUGUGUAUGUGAGAGAGAGAGAGAGAGAGAGAGGUUUGUCCCAUAUAUCUUGUUCCAGCAGCCAUAUAUCUUGUGGUCUACAGCCUAAAGCAUGAUUUCCCUUGAAGUCUUGGGGUUGUUUAAAGGAGAGUCCCUUCAAUAUAAAACCUCUGAAAUAUUAGUGAGAAUGGCUCACUAAUGUGAACAAUGUUUAAAUUAUUUAUUUAUAUAUAGAAUUACUGAAUAUUAGUACUGGGAAAAUUUAUAGAAAUCAUCUAGUCUUACCCUUCAUCUUACAUAUAAGAAAAAUGGUCUUUUCUUCUAAUCACAUUUACAAAAUAUGAUAUAAACCUUGACCAUGAAUGUAUGAGCCUAAUUAGAGAAACAGAAAAUCAGCAUGUCAGUUUUCCUUCAUUCAAAAUAACAUAGUCUUUCUAAGCAGUCAUUCUGGAGUUAACAUGCCUAGUUCAGAGCCGCUGUGGAUGCUCAAAUCAUUUCUGGAAUUGCCUUCAGGACACAAUUAUGAGAAAGUCAGACUUCCAAUAUUUUGAUCAUGCCUUGUGUCUUCCUAAGUGUCCUUAUCCCACUGGAUUGUGUCUCUUACUCCCAAGACUUAUUCCAAAUGAUUUUUUGACUCUUUUCAUUAAUCAAAUUCACCCCAAACCAGAAAGUUUUGCCAUUAGCGUAGAUAUUAAAAAUAUUACUGGCUGGGAAAGCACUCCUCAAAGCAGAGGUUCUAAAUUAAUUUAUCUGUUCUUUUACCAUUUGCUCACUCACUCACUCAUGGACCCAUUCAAUCAUAGAAUAUUUAAGAUUUAUAUGCCCAGAAUUAUAAUAGUGCCUAGGCCUUGAUAAUUAGUGAAUUUGUACUUGGGGUGAAUGUGUAAGUGUCAAAAGGUAACUAUUAUGAAGGAGAAAAUAAUCGAUUUAAUAUGUAAAUUCUGGGGAGGCAUUUAAAAAAUCAGUAAUCUUCAAGUUAUAUCUUGUGUAUCAUCUGUGUUGGAUACUCUAAUUUGGGGGGAAAGAGGCUCCAGACAGUUUGCUAAAUACUAUUUUGAAAGUUAUUUUUGGGCAUUGUAAAAUACCUUGCUUCAUACCCCAAAGAAUAAGAUAUGACAAUCUGACAUCGAUUGUCUGAAAGUACUAAUUGCAUUUAAAAUUCUUUAAGUUAACUACAACCUCCCAGACUGCAAAGCAAAUUUCCAAACCCCAGGUCAUACUUUUGUAUGUAUGUAAAAGCUUUAGCAUUUUAGGGAAAAAAAUCAAUCUGUAUUUCAAAAAUAAACUUUGAGGUUUGAAAAUAAUAACAAUAUUCAUAAUGGUAGUAUUAACAUCUAUUAUGUAUAACUUAAUCUCAACAUAAUUUAUUGAAUUAGAAUGAACCUGGAACACUUUUUGAUGAAUUGGUAUCCUAGAGGCUGUUUCCUUGGGCCUUAACUGCUGGAGGAUUAGGUAAUCAGGGAUUCCAAGUGUUGUGAUCUUUUUUCUGAUGACGCCACAGUCUUCAGUGUAAAAGUUCAGAAGCCUAAAAGAACAAGUGAUCCUGAAAGUAGCUGAUUCCAGACAAGAAAAUUAUAUUAGAACUCAUGAUAUGGUUUUUUAAAGUAUUUGUUAUUACUCAGAAGGGUUCAUGAAUCAGUUUCCACUACCUCUAUUCCUUCUAUUGAAGCUUUCCUCAAAUCUACUUGUGAUUCCUGAUAGCUCACUGGCAACUGUACCAAGGUGGCCACUGUAUCAUCUACUGAUCCUUCUGCACCUAGCACUCUUGGCUCCAGAUAACGCACAGAAACCUAUUUUCUCACCAGCUGUCAUUUCUUCUAGGGCAUGCAGUUCUAUGUUCACAGUUCAUGUGUAAAAAUAAAACCAAAUUCCUGGAUUAUCAAUAUCAGUUCUUUACCUGUGCAUAAAAGAAUAUCAUGAAGUAAUUGAACUUAUCUGUUGAUAUAAAAACACAGAUCCAAUUCGUGUCUGUGGAUGCUGCAAGGACUGGCUCACUGGAGCCAAACCAUGUGGCGGAAACUCCUGAAAUUGGUGGAAAAAGUGGAAUAUGGCAGAUUGGGUAGGUAGGAGAACAAUUUUGGAGAUUUUGUUUCUCAUGUUAAAGUGUCUGCAUUUUAUUUGCUGUACCCUGCCUACUCUGGUUUUAAGGAUUUUUUGACUUCUUCGAAAAGCACUGAAUAAUCUCUUUGCCGGGUCUAGAUUUUUUGAUGAGUACUGUGUAAAAUUGUCAAUAUUCAAUGGAUUAUUUAAUAAUAAAUUAAGAAUUACACUCAUAAAAGUAUUGUCUAAUGAAAGGUAAUGUAGACAAACGAACACUUUUUUAAAAAAAGAGGUGGAACAAAAGGUGGUAGAUUACAUGUAAAUUAGGUUGGAAAGUGAUACAAAUGACUUGUAAAUAACCACUGAAGCACAAGGGAACCACUUCUUUAUCAGUUCCUUUCUAACUUCUGAAGAUGUACUGCUGGUAAAGCACAUGUAUGGUUGGCAUUUCUUUUAUUUUCUUUCUCUUUUUUACUAGUUGGGCAAAAAAAUUUCCUAGGCAGGUAGCUAACUAUGAAAUUGUUUCCUGCGCUAAUUCUGAACAAAAAGACCAAGAAUGAAUUUACUUAUGAAUGUCCUUUUCUAAUGUGCCCUCUUAUGCUUCUCCUCCAAUGUAAGCAAGCUUACUGUCUUUUUCUAAGAUUAGCGCAUGGAUUCUAUCUUUAGCCAAAAGGUUUCAUCACUAGAUGAACUUCUCAUGUGUUUAGUUCUUCCAAAUGAUGCUCUUGCUUCCUGGGUAUCCAACCUGACUUGCUGGUUUAUAUUGGCUUCCAAAAUUUUAGAGUGAUAGGGUAUCGGAGAGGGAAAUUUGCACAUUCCUUAUGCAAUUUGUUAGUAUGCAUUCAGCUGUAACUCAGAAAAUAUUCCUGAUCAACAUGCAUCCAAACACUAAAGACAUUUAUAACCUCACAUAGCAGUAAGUCUUGAAGUGAUAAAUUCAGGUUUGGUGCAGCCACUCAGUGGCUCUUCUUAAUAUAUUGACUUAAUUCUUAGGCUUAUCCUCUUAGCUAAAAGAUCGCUACCUCAAGUCUACAUAUAAUUGAAUGCGGCAGCAAAAUGGGAGGAGAGAGUUCUCUUUAUAAUCCCCUUUUAGAAGGUGGAAAAUAGUAAGAACACAAGUUGAAUUUUCCUUCUAUUUCUUUGUUCAGAACUGUGCCACACAGCUACUCUUACCUGCAAGGGAAGCUGGAAAAAAGAAUAUUUAGUAUUUUGUGCUUCUAGAGAGUGAGGCAAGUUCUGAUAGUAAGAAAGAAGAGAUAGCCGAAGUAGCUGUCAUAAAAUUAUGUUAGUCAAGACAGAUUAGUUAUGCUACAACAUUAGAGAUUUAUUUCUUGAUCUCAUGACCUGUCCAUUGGGGUUAGCUGAAGGAUCUGUUCCACAUCUCAUUUGAGUUCACAGGCUGACAGAGACUUCCAUUCUAAACAUUCUUCCAUUGUGAGGGAACAGGAACAGGUGCUUCCAUGAUUAGGGGGAAGGGACAGGGAGAAUCAUGCAAUAGUUCGUGAAGCUUCCACAUUACUGUGCAUUUUUCACUGGGCAGGUGACAGAACCAGGAUAUUUGCAAGCAGCCCUAAAGGUUACCACAGUGGGCAAGCAAUAAUAUCUGCAUAUCCAAAUUAACUGCUCUUUGAAAUAAUUAGAACUCGUUUUACUCUAGAAAAUAUAUUUUGGAAAAGAACACACAUUGGAAUAAUGACGAAAAAAAUUGCUUUCUGUAUUGCAAAAUGUAUACGUUCCUUUAACAGAUUUAUAUCAAGCACCUAUAUACUUUAUGGCAGAAAUUAUGCUAAAUCCUAAGAAUGAAACAAUAAUGAAGGCAAAGCUAUUCCCUGCCAAAAGGAACUUAGAGUUUAACGAACAAAGCAAACGGAUGAACAGGUAAUUACUGUACAGAGUGACCCAUAUUGUUAUUGUUCAGGGAAUUAGAGAGGGCACCUAAUAUGGUCUUGGGGAUGUUUCAGUAAGUUUCCUGGAAGAAAUAACAUAUAAGCUAAGACUUAAAAGAUAUGUAGAAAUUAGCUAGAAGGAAGGCAAUGGUGUGUGCAUGUAUGUGUGUAUUAGUUUGUGUUUGUGUUUGUGUACUGGGCAAAUAGACUAUUCCAUGUAGAGGGAAUAUUGAGUACUUUAUCAAGACUAUAGUUAGAGUAUAAGGAAAGAGUUGACAGUGAGGCAGCACCAAACUUUACCUUCAUAAAUAGCAAUUUGGUUUUAUACUUGUAUUAGCAUUUUUCCCCCUUGACAUCAAUGUCCUUGAAUGUAUUUGCCAUUUGCUCUAAUAAUAAAAUACACUUUCUAUAACCAAAAA